ACAGAGGAAGAGGCAAUACUACCCGAGACUAGAUGCGGACCGUCUCUGGCAACCAGGAAAAGGCAAAUACAAAGAGAGGUCUGCUGGUCACAGCGGGGCACCUCGAGGAGAGGACGACUAGGAGCACACGGCCCGGAAAGGUCCAGAAUAACUGUGCUUGAAGAAGAAAAUUCCCAACAUGGACAAACCACGCAAAGAAAAUGAAGAAGAGCCGCAGAGCGCGCCCAAGACCGAUGAGGAGAGGCCUCCGGUGGAGCACUCUCCCGAAAAGCAGUCCCCCGAGGAGCAGUCUUCGGAGGAGCAGUCCUCGGAGGAGGAGUUCUUUCCUGAGGAGCUCUUGCCUGAGCUCCUGCCUGAGAUGCUCCUCUCGGAGGAGCGCCCUCCGCAGGAGGGUCUUUCCAGGAAGGACCUGUUUGAGGGGCGCCCUCCCAUGGAGCAGCCUCCUUGUGGAGUAGGAAAACAUAAGCUUGAAGAAGGAAGCUUUAAAGAAAGGUUGGCUCGUUCUCGCCCGCAAUUUAGAGGGGACAUACAUGGCAGAAAUUUAAGCAAUGAGGAGAUGAUACAGGCAGCAGAUGAGCUAGAAGAGAUGAAAAGAGUAAGAAACAAACUGAUGAUAAUGCACUGGAAGGCAAAACGGAGCCGUCCUUAUCCUAUUUAAUGUGUUCGGCCUUUAAUUCUGUUUUGCCUGCUAAUAGUAUUGCCAUUGCCACCUGGACUUUCUGUUUGCAUUUUCUUAAUGCCUUUUCCCAUAUUCUGAAUUUUAACUUUUUGUGAGGCUUUAUUUUAGAUGUUUAGCAUGUAACUCGCUUAAAGUUGAGGUUUCCCCCUAAAAUCUACAAGUUUCCCUCUUUCAGUCAUGAGCCCUACACAUUUGCAUGAAAGAUGUACAUUAUAUAUUGUGAAACGAAAAAAGCAAUUUUCAAAUGGUAUAUAUUGUAUCCCAUUUUUGUAAAAAAAAUGUAUAUUUAUAUAUUAAUAUGCAAAGAAAAAGCUAAAAGUAUAGACUUCAAAGGCAUAACAGUGGUUGUGUGGUAAGAUAAUAGGUGAUUUUUUAAAUUUUUGUUUUAUCUGAAUUUCUCAUUUUUUCAGGACAAACGUUUUACUUGUGUUGCAAAAAUAUAUAAUGAAAAAAUCACACAAUUUUGAAGAAAACUGUCAAUCAGCUUAUAACGACAAUGUGGCACUUAAUAAAUACUUGUCAGAACUUUAAAAAAA